GCAUUUCUCCUCUGUGCUCACUGCCACACGCAGCUCAACCUGAGCUACACAGCCAGAUGCGAGAUGCUUCUCUGCUGAUCUGAGUCUGCCUGCAGCAUGGACCUUGGUCUUCCCUGAAGCAUCUCCAGGGCUGGAGGGACGACUGCCAUGCACCGAGGGCUCAUCCAUCCGCAGAGCAGGGCAGUGGGAGGAGACGCUAUGACCCCCAUCGUCACAGUCCUGAUCUGUCUCAGGCUGAGUCUGGGCCCCCGGACCCACGUGCAGGCAGGGACCCUCCCCAAGCCCACACUCUGGGCUGAGCCAGGCUCUGUGAUCACCCAGGGGAGUCCCGUGACCCUCUGGUGUCAGGGGAUCCUGGAGACCCAGGAGUACCGUCUGUAUAGAGAAAAGAAAACAGCACCCUGGAUUACACGGAUCCCACAGGAGAUUGUGAAGAAGGGCCAGUUCCCCAUCCCAUCCAUCACCUGGGAACACACAGGGCGGUAUCGCUGUUUCUACGGUAGCCACACUGCAGGCUGGUCAGAGCCCAGUGACCCCCUGGAGCUGGUGGUGACAGGAGCCUACAUCAAACCCACCCUCUCAGCUCUACCCAGCCCUGUGGUGACCUCAGGAGGGAACGUGACCCUCCAUUGUGUCUCACAGGUGGCAUUUGGCAGCUUCAUUCUGUGUAAGGAAGGAGAAGAUGAACACCCACAAUGCCUGAACUCACAGCCCCGUACCCAUGGGUGGUCCCGGGCCAUCUUCUCUGUGGGCCCCGUGAGCCCGAGUCGCAGGUGGUCGUACAGGUGCUAUGCUUAUGACUCGAACUCUCCCCAUGUGUGGUCUCUACCCAGUGAUCUCCUGGAGCUCCUGGUCCUAGGUGUUUCUAAGAAGCCAUCACUCUCAGUGCAGCCAGGUCCUAUAGUGGCCCCUGGGGAGAGCCUGACCCUCCAGUGUGUUUCUGAUGUCAGCUACGACAGAUUUGUUCUGUAUAAGGAGGGAGAACGUGACUUCCUCCAGCUCCCUGGCCCACAGCCCCAGGCUGGGCUCUCCCAGGCCAACUUCACCCUGGGCCCUGUGAGCCGCUCCUACGGGGGCCAGUACAGAUGCUCCGGUGCAUACAACCUCUCCUCCGAGUGGUCGGCCCCCAGCGACCCCCUGGACAUCCUGAUCGCAGGACAGUUCCGUGGCAGACCCUUCAUCUCGGUGCAUCCGGGCCCCACGGUGGCCUCAGGAGAGAACGUGACCCUGCUGUGUCAGUCAUGGGGGCCGUUCCACACUUUCCUUCUGACCAAGGCGGGAGCAGCUGAUGCCCCCCUCCGUCUCAGAUCAAUACACGAAUAUCCUAAGUACCAGGCUGAAUUCCCUAUGAGUCCUGUGACCUCAGCCCACUCGGGGACCUACAGGUGCUACGGCUCACUCAGCUCCAACCCCUACCUGCUGUCUCACCCCAGUGACUCCCUGGAGCUCAUGGUCUCAGGAGCAGCUGAGACCCUCAGCCCACCACAAAACAAGUCCGAUUCCAAGGCUGGAGCAGCUAACACCCUCAGCCCAUCACAAAACAAGACUGCCUCACACCCCCAGGAUUACACAGUGGAGAAUCUCAUCCGCAUGGGCAUAGCUGGCUUGGUCCUGGUGGUCCUCGGGAUUCUGCUAUUUGAGGCUCAGCACAGCCAGAGAAGCCUCUGAGAUGCAGCCGGGAGGUGAACAGCAGAGAGAAGAAUGUACCCUUCAGAGUGGUGGAGCCUUGGGAACAGAUCUGAUGAUGCCAGGAGGUUCCGGGAGACAAUUUAGGGCUGAUGCUAUCUGGACUGUCUGCCAAUCAUUUUUAGAGGGAGGAAUCAGUGUUGGAUUGCAGAGACAUUUUCUGGAGUGAUCCAUGAAGGACCAUUAACCUGUGAUACCUUUCCUCUCUAUUAAUGUUGACUUCCCUUGGUUGGAUCCUCUUCUUUCCCCACCCCCAGACAGACAUGAGGCUACAUCCCACAUGGCAGCGUUGGGUCCACACCUCUGCACAUCUGUGUGCUCUGGUCCAUGGUGUGUAACACAGUCUUCUUUAUUACUCAUUGCCAUACUCCCUGGUGUGCUUUACUGAGCCUCCAUCUCUUCAAUUCAGAGUUCCAAACGUGCUUCAGUAACUAAAUCAAUGGGAGAGUAUCGGAUUUCAACCAGGAAAAGAUAAAUCCACCCUGAUGCCCUGACACCCUCUCUGAACCCUACGAGCCCUUCCCUCCUUCUCACAUGCUACCUGUGCAGCUUCUCCUUAGAUCAUUGUGUAACCAUCACUGCCAUCCUGUUCCACACAUGGUCAUCACCCUACACCCAUUCAGCAGCCACUCCCCAUUCCCUCUUCCCUCCAGCACCUGCUAACCACAAAUGUGCUUUCUGUCUCUACGGAUUUGCCUAUUCUGUCUGAAAACAUUUCAAUCUCCUUUGACCUGUGAGCUCCUCACUUCGAGACUUCCUGCCUUUCCAGGCAGAACCAAAGUACACCACGUCAAAAGCAAUGAUAGGCAUUUGCAGUGUGUUGGUGAUCCACGAAAGGAAAAUCACGGAAGCAGGAUAGAAAUCCAGCUGCAGACAAGACCUCAGGUCGAUGAAUCUUGACAAGCAGUUGAGCUGUUUUUUUCUACUCACCUAGGACAGUCAGGCAGAAGUAUGCAAAAUGACUGGGGCUGAUUCUUUUCUGAAUUGUCGCAAACAGCAAGAGGACUUGAGUCCUAGCAUUAAAGAGUUCAACAUGUCUAGGUCCAAGACCACUGUUGUGUUUGAAGGAUGUAAAACCCUGCUGCAUAGGAUGGAAUAUUUGGAGGGAGGAUCCUGAAAAACAUGAGGGAUCAAAUAGUCCUCAACUUUCUAGGACAAAGGGAGCAGCUAUUUGCCAUCUACCCUCCAGAAUAAAGAAAUCUUAUCAUUCACCAUCUACCCUCUAGAAUAAAGAAAUCUUAUCAUUCGCCAUCUACCCUGUAGAAUAAAGAAAUCUUAUCAUUCACCGUCUACCCUCUAGAGUAAACAAAUCUUAUCAUUCACCAUCUACCCUCUAGAAUAAAGAAAUCUUAUCAUUCGCCAUCUACCCUCUAGAAUAAAGAAAUCUUAUCAUUCACCGUCUACCCUCUAGAGUAAACAAAUCUUAUCAUUCGCCAUCUACCCUCUAGAAUAGAGAAAUCUUAUCAUUCAUCAUCUACCCUCCAGAAUAAAGAAAUGUUAUCAUUUGCCAUCUACCCUCUAGAAUAAAGAAAUCUUAUUAAGGACA